AGUUCCCCUUUCCCUUGAACCGCUCACUUCACAGCCCUUCGCCCCCGGGAAGAAGAAACAUUUCCCGAAGCGCACUCCUCAGCCCUCCUUCCCCACGCGCUCGCCCUCCCCUCCCCCUGCUUUUCUUGGGGGAGGGGGGCUGUCGCCUUGGAUUGAAGGCCAUUGAUUUGUAUGUAUUUGUCCCAGCGCUGGAGGCUGCCCCAGCCGCCGCGCCGGUGCCGCCGCUGCCAGUGGAGUUGCCUCCCCGCUUCCCUAGGGUGGUUCGGCUCCACCAAACAUGUCGGCUCCUGUCGGGCCCCGGGGCCGCCUGGCUCCCAUCCCGGCGGCCUCUCAGCCGCCUCUGCAGCCCGAGAUGCCUGACCUCAGCCACCUCACGGAGGAGGAGAGGAAAAUCAUCCUGGCCGUCAUGGAUAGGCAGAAGAAAGAAGAGGAGAAGGAGCAGUCCGUGCUCAAGGUCAAAGAAGAACACAAACCACAACUGACACAGUGGUUUCCCUUUAGUGGAAUCACUGAACUGGUAAAUAACGUUCUUCAGCCCCAGCAAAAACAACAAAAUGAAAAGGAGCCCCAGACAAAACUGCAUCAGCAGUUUGAAAUGUAUAAAGAGCAGGUAAAGAAGAUGGGAGAAGAAUCACAGCAACAGCAAGAACAGAAGGGUGAUGCGCCAACCUGUGGUAUCUGCCACAAAACAAAGUUUGCUGAUGGAUGUGGCCAUAACUGUUCAUAUUGCCAAACAAAGUUCUGUGCUCGUUGUGGAGGUCGAGUGUCAUUACGCUCAAACAAGGAGGACAAAGUGGUUAUGUGGGUAUGUAAUUUGUGCCGAAAACAACAAGAAAUCCUCACUAAAUCAGGAGCAUGGUUUUAUAAUAGUGGAUCUAAUACACCACAGCAACCUGAUCAAAAGGUUCUUCGAGGGCUAAGAAAUGAGGAGGCACCUCAGGAGAAGAAACCAAAACUACAUGAGCAGACCCAGUUCCAAGGACCCUCAGGUGACUUAUCUGUACCUGCAGUGGAGAAAAGUCGAUCUCAUGGGCUCACAAGACAGCAUUCUAUUAAAAAUGGGUCAGGCGUGAAGCAUCACAUUGCCAGUGACAUAGCUUCAGACAGGAAAACUUCCUCUGAACUUCUGAACUCCAAGAUUAUUUCAAGGAAAAGAAGCCCAUCUGUGUCCAGAGAUCAGAAUAGAAGAUACGACCAAAGGGAAGAAAGAGAGGAAUAUUCACAGUAUGCUACUUCGGAUACCGCAAUGCCUAGAUCUCCAUCAGAUUAUGCUGAUAGGCGAUCUCAACAUGAACCUCAGUUUUAUGAAGACUCUGAUCAUUUAAGUUAUAGGGACUCCAACAGGAGAAGUCAUAGGCAUUCCAAAGAAUAUAUUGUAGAUGAUGAGGAUGUGGAAAGCAGAGAUGAAUACGAAAGGCAAAGGAGAGAGGAAGAGUACCAGUCACGCUACCGAAGUGAUCCGAAUUUGGCCCGUUAUCCAGUAAAGCCACAACCCUAUGAAGAACAAAUGCGGAUCCAUGCUGAAGUGUCCCGAGCACGGCAUGAGAGAAGGCAUAGUGAUGUUUCUUUGGCAAAUGCUGAUCUGGAAGAUUCCAGGAUUUCUAUGCUAAGGAUGGAUCGACCAUCAAGGCAAAGAUCUAUAUCAGAACGUAGAGCUGCCAUGGAAAAUCAGCGAUCUUAUUCAAUGGAAAGAACUCGAGAGGCUCAGGGACCAAGUUCUUAUGCACAAAGGACCACAAACCAUAGUCCUCCUACCCCCAGGAGGAGUCCACUACCCAUAGAUAGACCAGACUUGAGGCGUACUGACUCACUACGGAAACAGCACCACUUAGAUCCUAGCUCUGCUGUAAGAAAAACAAAACGGGAAAAAAUGGAAACAAUGUUAAGGAAUGAUUCUCUCAGUUCAGACCAGUCAGAGUCAGUGAGACCUCCACCACCAAAGCCUCAUAAAUCAAAGAAAGGCGGUAAAAUGCGCCAGAUUUCGUUGAGCAGUUCAGAGGAGGAAUUGGCUUCCACGCCUGAAUAUACAAGUUGUGAUGAUGUUGAGAUUGAAAGUGAGAGUGUAAGUGAAAAAGGGGACAGUCAAAAGGGAAAAAGAAAAACUAGUGAGCAGGCAGUUUUGUCGGACUCUAACACCAGGUCUGAGAGACAAAAGGAAAUGAUGUACUUUGGUGGCCACUCUUUGGAAGAGGAUUUGGAAUGGUCUGAACCUCAGAUUAAGGACUCUGGGGUAGAUACGUGUAGUAGCACAACCCUUAACGAGGAGCAUAGCCAUAGUGAUAAGCACCCUGUAACCUGGCAACCAUCUAAAGAUGGAGAUCGUUUAAUUGGUCGCAUUUUAUUAAAUAAGCGUCUAAAAGAUGGAAGUGUACCUCGAGAUUCAGGAGCAAUGCUUGGCUUGAAGGUUGUAGGAGGAAAGAUGACUGAAUCAGGUCGGCUUUGUGCAUUUAUUACUAAAGUAAAAAAAGGAAGUUUAGCUGAUACUGUAGGACAUCUUAGACCAGGUGAUGAAGUAUUAGAAUGGAAUGGAAGACUACUGCAAGGAGCCACAUUUGAGGAAGUGUACAACAUCAUUCUAGAAUCCAAACCUGAACCACAAGUAGAACUUGUAGUUUCAAGGCCUAUUGGAGAUAUACCGCGAAUACCUGAUAGCACACAUGCACAACUGGAGUCCAGUUCUAGCUCCUUUGAAUCUCAAAAAAUGGAUCGUCCUUCUAUUUCUGUUACCUCUCCCAUGAGUCCUGGAAUGUUGAGGGAUGUCCCACAGUUCUUAUCAGGACAACUUUCAAGCCAAAGCCUUAGUAGAAGAACAACGCCUUUUGUUCCUAGGGUUCAGAUAAAACUAUGGUUUGACAAGGUUGGUCACCAAUUAAUAGUUACAAUUUUGGGAGCAAAAGAUCUCCCUUCCAGGGAAGAUGGGAGGCCAAGGAAUCCUUAUGUUAAAAUUUACUUUCUUCCAGACAGAAGUGAUAAAAACAAGAGAAGAACUAAAACAGUAAAGAAAACAUUGGAACCCAAAUGGAACCAAACAUUCAUUUAUUCUCCAGUCCACCGAAGAGAAUUUCGGGAACGAAUGCUAGAGAUUACCCUUUGGGAUCAAGCUCGUGUUCGAGAGGAAGAAAGUGAAUUCUUAGGCGAGAUUUUAAUUGAAUUAGAAACAGCAUUAUUAGAUGAUGAGCCACAUUGGUACAAACUUCAGACGCAUGAUGUCUCUUCAUUGCCACUUCCCCACCCUUCUCCAUAUAUGCCACGAAGACAGCUCCAUGGAGAGAGCCCAACACGGAGGUUGCAAAGGUCAAAGAGAAUAAGUGAUAGUGAAGUCUCUGACUAUGACUGUGAUGAUGGAAUUGGUGUAGUAUCAGAUUAUCGACAUGAUGGUCGAGAUCUUCAAAGCUCAACAUUAUCAGUGCCAGAACAAGUAAUGUCAUCAAACCACUGUUCACCAUCAGGGUCUCCUCAUCGAGUAGAUGUUAUAGGAAGGACUAGAUCAUGGUCACCCAGUGUCCCUCCUCCACAAAGUCGGAAUGUGGAACAGGGGCUUCGAGGGACCCGCACUAUGACCGGACAUUAUAAUACAAUUAGCCGAAUGGACAGACAUCGUGUCAUGGAUGACCAUUAUUCUCCAGAUAGAGACAGGGAUUGUGAAGCAGCAGAUAGACAGCCAUAUCACAGAUCCAGAUCAACAGAACAACGGCCUCUCCUUGAGCGGACCACCACCCGCUCCAGAUCCACUGAACGUCCUGAUACAAACCUCAUGAGGUCGAUGCCUUCAUUAAUGACUGGAAGAUCUGCCCCUCCUUCACCUGCCUUAUCGAGGUCUCAUCCUCGUACUGGGUCUGUCCAGACAAGCCCAUCAAGUACUCCAGUCGCAGGACGAAGGGGCCGACAGCUUCCACAGCUUCCACCAAAGGGAACGUUGGAUAGAAGUACUAUGGAUAUAGAGGAGAGAAAUCGCCAAAUGAAAAUUAACAAAUACAAACAGGUAGCCGGAUCAGAUCCCAGACUGGAACAAGAUUACCAUUCGAAGUAUCGAUCAGGAUGGGAUCCUCAUAGAGGGGCAGAUAAUGUUUCUACUAAAUCUUCGGACAGUGAUGUAAGUGAUAUAUCUGCGGUUUCAAGGACUAGUAGUGCUUCUCGUUUCAGCAGCACAAGCUACAUGUCUGUCCAAUCAGAACGCCCAGGAGGAAACAAGAAAAUCAGACCAAAGGGAAUAGAAGAGGGAGGGAAAGAAGGGGAUAAGCAUGAAGAGAUAGUUCAUGAGAAGGAAGAGGUAAAGGAAGAAAGAAUUAAUGAGAAUGAGAAAGGGAAAGAGAUUGCCAAAACGUGUAAUAAGGAGAAAAACAGAGAAUCAGGAGACGAGGAAAAAACACAAGAUAUACACGAGCAAGGGAAAGAAAAAGAACAGUGGAAUAAAGAGGAUUUGCAAAGGAGAUUCUCACAAGAUGAUACCAGUGUCUUUACAUCCAAAAUGCAAAGCAGACAAAUGGGCAUAUCAGGGAAGAACAUGACAAAAAGCACCAGCAUCAGUGGAGACAUGUGCUCACUGGAGAAGAAUGAUGGCAGCCAGUCUGACACUGCAGUGGGCACCUUGGGCACCAGUGGCAAAAAGCGGCGCUCUAGCCUUGGUGCCAAAAUGGUAGCUAUCGUUGGUCUGUCACGGAAAAGUCGCAGUGCUUCUCAGCUCAGCCAAACGGAAGCAGGAGGUAAAAAACUAAGGAGCACUGUCCAAAGAAGUACAGAAACAGGCCUGGCCGUGGAAAUGAGGAACUGGAUGACUCGACAGGCAAGCCGAGAGUCUACAGAUGGUAGCAUGAACAGCUACAGCUCAGAAGGAAAUCUGAUUUUCCCUGGUGUUCGCUUGGCCUCUGAUAGCCAGUUCAGUGAUUUCCUGGAUGGCCUUGGCCCUGCUCAGCUAGUGGGACGCCAGACUCUGGCAACACCUGCAAUGGGUGACAUUCAGGUAGGAAUGAUGGACAAAAAGGGACAGCUGGAGGUAGAAAUCAUCCGGGCCCGUGGCCUUGUUGUAAAACCAGGUUCCAAGACACUGCCAGCACCGUAUGUAAAAGUGUAUCUAUUAGAUAACGGAGUCUGCAUAGCCAAAAAGAAAACAAAAGUGGCAAGAAAAACGCUGGAACCCCUUUACCAGCAGCUAUUAUCUUUCGAAGAGAGUCCACAAGGAAAAGUUUUACAGAUCAUCGUCUGGGGAGAUUAUGGCCGCAUGGAUCACAAAUCUUUUAUGGGAGUGGCCCAGAUACUUUUAGAUGAACUAGAGCUAUCCAAUAUGGUGAUCGGAUGGUUCAAACUUUUCCCACCUUCCUCCCUAGUAGAUCCAACCUUGGCCCCUCUGACAAGAAGAGCUUCCCAAUCAUCUCUGGAAAGUUCAACUGGACCUUCUUACUCUCGUUCAUAGCAGCUGUAAAAAAAUUGUUGUCACAGCAACCAGCGUUACAAAAAAAAAAAAAAAAAUCACAGGUUGCAAACCCUGGUAACACUGCAUGCUUAAUGUUGUGUCUUCUGAGCCUGUUUCUAGGGAUACAAAGCAAUCCUGUGUUCUCAGAGGAAGUUGCACACAUUGUGCCCUAAAGAAGGCCCUCAGGUGAAAGAGCAGAGCUGUGAAGAACUAUCAGAUUUGGAAUUCAAUGACACUCGAGUUCUGGUCCAAUCUGAAGCCAUGGAUUAAUCUCAAAGAAUCAGUCAGUUUCAUGCAACAGAAGCCCUUUUCAAUGGCACCUUUAUAUUUUUAUCAUUCCUUUUUCUUCAUUUAUCUAACCCCAAAGCCCUGAUAUGCCACAGAAAUGGAGCUAUACAGCCAUGAAGCGGUGUUACAGGUGAGGAGUGUAAUCCUAGGAAGCAUCAGGUGAAAAGCAGGAGACCAAAGAAGUGGUCAGGAACAAUCAUCAGCCCUCCUCUGGGCGGGAAUCAGAGCAGUCAGUCCAGCAGGAAGAGUGGCAGACUUUGUAGCUCCAUGGGCACGUCAAUUACUAAUGCUAAGAUGUGUUGGACUCUGAAAAACAAAAUUCUGUGGCUACACUGUACUGAAUGAAAUUAAAGAAACUUUUUUUGCAUGGACACAGAUUAGCUGAAUACUUAAAUUAUUUUCUUGGGGCUGCAACUUGCAAAAAAAAAAAAAAGAAUAAAAAUCAGCCAUUUUCAACAAUUUAUAUUAUUUUUAAAAAUAAAUUUCACUAGUGCAUGGUUUUAAAAAGGAGAGAGAAUGCAACAGGGUGAUACAAAGAUACACCAUGUUUAUUCUUUAAUCAUAGUCUGUGUUUUGGCAGACAUUACAAAUGGAAAUACUUUCUAGAAGAUACUUAAAAUUCUCUUUAUGUGACAAAUAAGUAUAAUAUAUUCAAUUUAUUUCCAUGUUAAAUAUACAAAUCUUAUGAAGUUCAAUAUGUGCAAAUUUUUCACAUCUUUCUCCUUCUCUCACUUUACCUCUUCUCCCUCUUUUAAACUUUUCUUUCUCCCUGCCAGAGUGAACCUUAUACUAAAAAAUUACAAGUUUUGAUCUGAUCCUCUCUCAUACCCCAUGUUUGAUUCAGAGCUGUAGAUGCCUCUGAAUUUGCGAAUUUCUCAAGGGAAAAUUAACUUUAAGAGCUUUCUUUAUUUCAAGCAUGUUGAAAAGGAUUUUGCAACAUGACUUGGGAGUACAUUAAAGUAAGUCAGCAUGUAUUUGACGAAGAAGAUAUUUGAACUUUUGCAGUUUAUUGUACAGUGCAUGGUAAUUUUUUCACCUUUAAAAUUCAGUUUACAGGAAAAUUCUAAAAUCAUGUUGCCAUUGUGAUGUCCAAUAAAUUUGUUUUUAGCACCAGCAUUAUUCAUACAGGGGUUAAAGUAUUAUUUGUAGAAGGUCUUAGGUUUUGUUUGUUUUUUAAUCAUUUAAAGCAAUUUCUUUAGCCAGUUUCCAUUUACUAUGUGAAUAGAAGCACUGCUAAAAAUUGGGAACCCUGAAACACAGGGCUGUUUAUUAAUUCAUUUUUCUGUAGUAAAAUUCAAUUUUUCACAAAUUAUAUUUCUAAAGAAAUAUAGUAAACAUAAAUUUGCAACAAUUUUAAAGCUCCAGUUUUUAGGUGACUCAAAGAAAGUCAUUAUGCCUAUUAAUAGUUAUUUGAUGCCAUCACCAAAAGUCUAUGUGAAAAUCUCCUAAAGUCAAAACCCCUGCCUUUGGUUUUACAGACGGUUAUUACCAUUGGGUGGAGCUGCAAGGUCAAAUUUCUCCUAAGUUCCCCUAUUUAGAGGAAAAGUCACUGGUUAUUGUAAUAAACCACCCAUGGUUCUUUAUGUACAUUUUGAUAACACAUUAUUAUAGCUUGAUUUUAAUUUUUUGCAUUAAUUUUUGAAAUCCACAUACAUCUCAUUUGUUUAAAUUAAGGCCAUGCACAAAUAUUUUUUUUAGUUCAGUGCUGACCAUUAAAAACUAUCAUGCUUGAUACGGUGCAAAAGUUAAAAUGAGUAUCACUAAAAAUGCCUUCUUUUUAUGUGGUGCAAUAUGAAAUACACCAAGACUGUGUCUUGACAUUCUGAUGGACCCAGGUAAAGUUGUUAAAAGAACGAAUAAAACUUUAUUAAAAUAAUUUAGACACCUGUGUACCAGCAACAAUUGAUUUAAUAGACCUAUAGUGUCUAUACUAUCCCUUAGAAUAAAGGUUUAUGAUUUUCCUGAUACUAAGAUGCAGUCACAUAAUCUUUUGUGCAUAUUCCUAUACAAAUUAUUUCUAAUUUUAAUAAGAAGGACGUGACUACGGAAUAUUUGUACAUACUUGUCAUUAUGCAGUAUUUAUUUAAAAGUUGGUGUUUUUUUUUAAUUUUCACAUCUGCACCUCGACUUGUGGUUUAGUCAUGUAACUAGCACUAUGCCAGUGACCGUUGUUGCCCUGUACAUAGUAUGUUUGAAAAGUAAAGGGAAUUCCAGUUGGGAAAAAAGGGCAGAUUAGUCCUGUAAUGAACACCAACUAAUGUAAAUCAAAUUCAUUCUGGUGAUGGUAUUUAACACUUUAAAUAAAACAUUUUCUUUACAGGCGUCUGCAGUGCUUUCUCUGACUUUUCUCCCCACACAGCCCUGAGCCUGCUGCAGCUCAUUCCCUGAACUCAUGUGUCAUUUAAAGAAUGAAAUCACCGUCUCCUACUUCUCGAUAACAUAAGUGGACUGCUGGUCUUAGCAGCGGCCCUCAGUAGAGCAUUUCUUUAAAACGCCAAAGGAUUUCUGCUCACACUAUGAAAAGGUGCUGUUUUUUAAAAGGUUGUUAUUUUGGAUUGAGUUUCUUUCUGAUUAAAUGACUCAGCAACUCACAGAUUUUUUGAGUGAAAUUUUUAAUUUAGUCAUGGCCUUCACUGACAGCAUAGUCACAAAUACUCAGGCACAGGCUCUGCUAGCCCCUGGGUGAAGAUGGCGAAGGCAUAACUGGCUUUAUGCAGCAUAUGUGUUUCUGCUAAAGUGUCAGUUUUGCUUUGUGGGGAGUGGAGGGUGUGUUUUCGGGAUGGGGAGACGUGGUAACCUGACAUGUAACAACCUGUCCGGAGACUAGCUUCUACGUGUGGAUAUGAAUGGGUGAGAGGAUUUCUCCAUAUCCUUCUGGGGCGAUUCCUCAACUGGGAGAAGGAAACCCUGCAGAGUUCUCAUGGGAGUCUGCUUCAGGUUUGAAAUUUAAGAGCUAGUUUGGAUUCAUGUUUAGUAAUCGAACUGAAAUCUAAGUCUAGCUGUCUCUCUAUUCUUGGAAACAACCAUUUCCUCCAUUUCCAAAGACUCAACUCGAGUCCAAUUCCCCCUAUCUGUCCCAUAUAUUUUUCCUUUAUCCCAUAUAUACCCCCUACUCUAGUGAAUUGUUUCUUUGUUGUUCAUUCCUGUUCUUUGUUGUUCAUAUACAUUCCUGUAUAUGAACAACAUUUUCCUUUAUCCCAUAUAUACCCCCUACUCUAGUGAAUUGUUUCUUUGUUGUUCAUUCCUGUUUCUUUGUUGUUCAUAUACAUUCCUGUUAUAAAAAUUCCCUUCCCUUUCUUAUGUGCCCUCUCCUGAAAAGCCCUUCUACUUUUCUCAAUAAUGAUCCAUGCGAGUCCCUUCUUGCAACUCCCAGCUCACGAAUGAGCUCUUUCGGCAACUCCUGACUAAACCCUAACAACAUGGCUGCCAUUGAUGCCAACACCUUCACUUUCCCAGGGACCCCAGAUGCCAAGGCUCCAUAGGCAACAAUAAAGGAUAUGAUGGUCCUGUAGUGGGUAUGAUAGAAUUAGGCAAGAGAUCACCAAAGCUGUCUGCCUACUACUGAUGUAAACCUUGACAUUCUGUGCACGUAAAAAUCAUGUGCUCAAUGUGUUUGUCUCAACUCCCUCAGCUCGUGAUGCCCUCAGGGUUCUGUGGGCAUUUAUGCACUGAAGAAACAGGAGUUCACACAUCCACCUCUGGACUGUGAAAUGUGUAUUGAGAAAUACUUUGCAAGAGAGAAUUUUUUUAAGUGAACAAACAACAAGUCUGUGCCACACACAUCUUCCAUAUGCCCUGACUCAGGUCACUUAAUCUCCAGGAUUUCAUUUCCUCACCUGGAAAAUAUGGAGUUUGAGGUAGAUUCUCAUCUAUCAUUAAAUCAACACUUUAACUAAAACGUAAGCUCCUUCAGGGCAGAGACCGUAUCUUCAGUAUCAAAAACAAUGUUUGACACAUAGCUGCUCAAUAAACAUCUGUCCAAUGAA